AGUGGCAAGAUGGCGUCCCUGGAUCGGGUGAAGGUACUGGUGUUGGGAGACUCAGGUGUUGGGAAAUCUUCGUUAGUCCAUCUCCUAUGCCAAAAUCAAGUGCUGGGAAAUCCAUCAUGGACUGUGGGCUGCUCAGUGGAUGUCAGAGUUCAUGAUUACAAAGAAGGAACCCCAGAAGAGAAGACCUACUACAUAGAAUUAUGGGAUGUUGGAGGCUCUGUGGGCAGUGCCAGCAGCGUGAAAAGCACAAGAGCAGUAUUCUACAACUCCGUAAAUGGUAUUAUUUUCGUACACGACUUAACAAAUAAGAAGUCCUCCCAAAACUUGCGUCGUUGGUCAUUGGAAGCUCUCAACAGGGAUUUGGUGCCAACUGGAGUCUUGGUGACAAAUGGGGAUUAUGAUCAAGAACAGUUUGCUGAUAACCAAAUACCACUGUUGGUAAUAGGGACUAAACUGGACCAGAUUCAUGAAACAAAGCGCCAUGAAGUUUUAACUAGGACUGCUUUCCUGGCUGAGGAUUUCAAUCCAGAAGAAAUUAAUUUGGACUGCACAAAUCCACGGUACUUAGCUGCAGGUUCUUCCAAUGCUGUCAAGCUCAGUAGGUUUUUUGAUAAGGUCAUAGAGAAGAGAUACUUUUUAAGAGAAGGUAAUCAGAUUCCAGGCUUUCCUGAUCGGAAAAGAUUUGGGGCAGGAACAUUAAAGAGCCUUCAUUAUGACUGAAUUACACUCAUCCUUUGGAAGAGUGAGCAAGCAGUGGCAGUUUUUCACAGCUCAUCUUGCUGUGUUCAAUUAUUACCAUCACAGCCUUUUAACAAAAUCAUCUUAAAAUGCUACCCUUCAGCCUUACCCUUUAAUGGAAAAAUGAAAGGAAGUGACAAUACGGGAGGUCCAAACUUUGUCCCUGUUCUCUGUGUUCCUUACCUUUCUGUCCCUGUGUAUAGAUUAUGUAAAAGCCUUGUGUAAAUAUGAGAUGUUGUCAAAAUGAUGCAGUAAAUGAGCAAUGACAGUGUACUGCAGAGAAAAUUUACUCUUGCCUAGAACUGGAGGGUUUUUAUGGGUCUGUAAUUUUCCCACACUCAUUGCUGAAAGCUUAAUUAAGUACUUCAAAAACGUAUCUCCAUUGUUUUACCUUCUUGAGGGGAACGGUCUUGUUAACCAGCCCUGAGUUGUCUACCCCAAACAAUCUCUGUCAUUUUCAAAGAUGCAAAAUGGUGUUAUUUAAUUGUCUCCACCAUUGUCACACACAGGAAUGCCUAAUAAUAGCAACCCUUGUCUCCCUCUUCUCUCCUUUGCAAAUGGCUCAGUGACUGGAAGAGGCGGACUAAUAGCCAGAGUUAAAUAUAAAUACAAAUUAAUAAUACAUAGAGAACAGCAAUACCAGAAAAAAAGAAUUCUGGUAAAAUGAUGUGAAAAAUUGACAGCUCCCUCACUCUUAAGGUUGCUGCUAUAUACAGUCUAGGUUUUCUGUUUGGAAAUAGGUAGGGUAAAAUCUAAGACCUGCACAAGGGCAGUGAGAGACAUUUACAGCCUCCUCUCUAUUUGUUUUUUUAAGGAAAAGUCAACUCCUGAAAUGUCCCUUAGCUAUAAUCAGAAAACUAAGAAUAUUAUUCUGUGUCAACAAUGUAUUUAUGGAGAGAAGUAAAAAUAAGUUCCACAGCAACACAUUUACAUGAAUUAUGAACUAGGAUUCUUGGAUUUCAUAAUCACUCCAAAGCUUUUUGGGGAUGGUGUGUGUGUGUGUGUGUGUCCGUAAUUGUUCAUCAUUACUUUUUUUAACCUAUCUUUUUGCUUGCUUAAUCUUCUCUGCCCCAGUUCUUCCUGAGUAUAUGAAUUUGAUUUCUAAAAACAAUUUAUUCAACACUCUAUCACCCGUAUUCUCUCUCUGGCUCUGCUGCAGGUCUCUGCACUCCUGAUUUUGCUCCAUACUUUUAAAUAACAAUAAUAAAUAUACAGUUUUCAUUUCUCAUUUAAAAAAUAGGUGGAAAACACCAAAUUCACUUUCUGUUCCAUUUUAAUUAGGUUUCAGAAGUAUCUUGGAAAUCAAGGUAUGCUGCAAGAGGAUAUUAAAAUAAGAAUGUUAGAGAGUCCUUUUAGAAAGGCAGUCUUGGGAAUUUGGAAAAGGAUUUUUAAAGCAGCUUUCAUCAGCUAGACUGUUCUCCAGCCUUUCUUUACUUCCUCUUUGAAAGGACAUAGCCCUGGUUUCUUUUUGACACAAAGGAAAGCUAUGCAAAUCAUGAUCUGUAUGUAGAAUUGGUCACAAGUAUGUUGUUGCAUAGGCUGUACAGUUGGGAAGUAGAAACCAAAUGCUACCCAGAGACCUAACCCAAUUAAGCUCUUUGUAUUUCUCCUUCAAGAAAUAAAUCUUCCUUCCUUCUUUCUUCCUCUUUCUUUUAAUUUUAAAAAAAUUCAUCCUGAUUUUUUUAUUUUCUAUCUUAUUUAAAAAAUAAAAAUAGGCCAGGCGCGGUGGCUCACACCUUUAAUCCCAACACUUUGGGAGGCGGGUCGAUCACUUGAUAUCAGGAGUUUGAGACCAGCCUGGCCAACAUAGGGAAACCCUGUCUCUACUAAAAAUACAAAAAUUAGCCAGGCCUGGUGGCACGCGCCUGUAAUCCCAGCUACUUGGGAGGCUGAGGCAGGAGAAUCACUUGAACCUGGGAGGUGGAGGUUGCAGUGAGUCAAGAUCGUGUCACUGCACUCCAGCCUAGGUGACAGAGUGAGACUCCAACUAAAAGAAAAUAAAUAAAUAAAUAUAUAAAUAUAUAAAUAAAUAAUAAAAGUAAACUAUUGCUGAUGACUCCAGGGUCAAUCUGGAAAAAUUAACAGUAUUCCUCAACUCCAUUACUUUCUGCAGCCAAGCUUGAUUCCUUGAAUUAUAGUUUUCUAAGAAAAAAUAGUUUUUAAUAAUCUAAGGUAAAUUUGUUGCAAUUAUUAGCAGCAGCAUAAUAAGGCUUUUUGCGCAAAUGAAUGUUAUUAGCUAGAGUUAUUCAAAAAAGAAUGAAGCACAAUUUUUGCUAGGACUUCUUGAGAACUAUUCAUAAAAAUGCUUUUAGAUAAUAAACAAGUAUAAAUGUCAAAAUAUUUUUUUAAAAGUAUAAUUGGCCAGGUGCUGGCUCACGCCUAUAAUCCCAGCACUCUAGGAGACUGAGGCAGGAGGAUCACUUGAGCUCGGGAGUUUGAGGCUGCAGUGAUUCAUGAUUGCACCACUGCCUUCCAGCAGCCUGAUGACAGAGUGGGACUCCAUCUCUUUACAUAUGUAUAUCUUACUCUCUUGAUGGGACAAGUUGGUAGAAAUAAAGAUUUUUUUUUUCUGUUGUGAUUUCGGUGUCUGACCAAUUUUCUGACUCAUUGUGAAGGUGACCAGAUAUGAAGGCAUAUAUAUGACUACUCCUCUGUCCCUUAGGUGUAUAAGACUUAGCUGGAAUCCAACUAAAGAUUUGGGCUGGUCUCUCCAUCUUAACGUUGAUGGGAUUCAGGACACAUAACCCCAAAAUAUUGCACCCUGUUAUUUGAGAAAACUGCAGAAGCAAGGUUUCUCAUACCUUCCCCUUACCCCUUCUCCCCUGAAGCAGGCCAUAAACCCUAAGUGACUGUUCCCUGAAGUAGAUCAUAAAACCUUCAUUCCAUAGGUACCCUUUAUCCUCACAGAUACAGAGACACCAAGAAGAAUCUGGACAAAUAGGACUUGCUAAGUUCUCCACAGUUUAUUACCAUUAGAUUAUGUCCUUUUGUCCUCUGAUUAUACUUCUGCAUAAGACUGUACAUAAAAAUACACAAGUUUUCCUAUUUCUUUUUUGUCUUCAUUUCUGAAGAUUCCUGUCAUGUAAAACUUACAGUAAAUAAAUGUGUGUGCUUUUCUCAAUAAUCUGUCUUUCGUUAUAGGUGCCUCAUUUGUGAACCUAGUGAUGGGUGAAGAAAGAAAGCUCUUCUCCGCUACAGUGCUCUAAGAAAAGCUAUUCCCAAAAGAGUUGAUCCAUAUUAGCUUUAGCUCGGGUUCUUAGAAUUCCUCAAACUUGAGGCAUUCAUGAUAUAAUCCAGGUGCCCUGACACUUGUUUUUCUGUUCAUUCUGACAUGGACUUCAUGGAAAUGAUGUGCAGGGACAUCAGACUGAGGUGAAGAGCUCCUAAUUGCUCCUUGUAAUCAGAGUUUCUGAGUCCUCAUUUCAAUAGUUUGCAGUAGCACCCACCAUAGGUAGGACCUUGUAUGGGUUACUAGAUGGUGGCUUAAUUGAAUUUUUUAAAGCACAGGUGACAUCAUAUUUUAAGAAGUUUAAAGGUCUAACAGGGUGUCUGCAUUGGUUUAAUAUAUGUUAAAAUUCAAAGGAGGAGUCUGUUUUGGGGAAAGGAGGAGAAGGAAAUUAGAAAUUCAUUUCUCCGCAGUCCCAAGACUGAGCUAAAUCACUGUGGUGGGAGAGGAAGGGUCGCAGGAAGUCUAACCCUGUGUCUCAAAUAUUUCACAACAUGUUUGCCUACACAAAAUAUCUGAUGUUAGGGUCAGCUGGGGCUGCUCCAUAGCAUAGUAAAGGAAUUGGACAUCCAGUUACAAUUAAUCUGCACCUCCAUUAAGGACUCACAUGGAGGGCUUUCAAACUCUGAAGUGUGUAAGAAUCCCCUGAAGUGCUUGCUGAAAAUGCAGAUUCCACGAUUUCCUCUCUCUUCCCUUACUCUCCCCUUUCUAUAUGUAUAGGAUAAGGCCAGGAUUUUGUAUUUUUAACAGACAAGCCAGAUUUUUCUCAUGCAGAUAAGUCAGGAUCUAGCCUUUAAGAAAGACAAAUAAACUCAUCAAAAAGUAGGGAAUAUAGAUUGUGAACUCUGUACUUUAUGAGUGCCAUUAUAGCAGAAUUCAUCAAAGCGCAUCUUUGACUGCCUCAACCUGAUCUCACCUUAAUGAACUGAUCCACUCCUCCCCACUCAAAGCUACAUAUGCCAAAUUAAACAUGAGAUGAUUGUCAUGUCUUCUGUUGGCAAAACAAGUAUUUGUCUUUCAUGUAUUGCUAUCAUUUUUAUUACUGCCACUGUUUUUCCCCUGGGUUCUGUUUUUAAUCCAAAUAUAUUUAUUUCUAACCAGUGCCUUGCCAUCUUACACACAGCCCCCUCUCUAGUACUGUGUUUUCUCAGCUGGCUAAUCACUAAGCUUUACCGAGGUCAUCAAUAACUAAUGACAAAGAAUGGAACCCCUAAACUCCAACCAAGGUGUAAAACCUCGCUCAGUACCAUCAAGUAUAUCAGGUAAUCUCUCCGUUCCAUCUUUUUCUCGGAGACAUCUGUCCUGGAGUCCUCUGAUGCCUAACUCCGUUUUGGAGUGAUUACUCUGUAGACCUGUCACACCCUGCUUCACAUUACCUUGUAGCAAUUCCUGGAUGUAAUGUUUUCCACUUUCUAUCCAACUCUUACUCUAUGGGACUUGGCUCAGACAUAGUCUUCUCUGGGAAGCCCUCCCUGGCUCUGCUCGUCUGGGCUACGUGCCCACUAGUGCUUCCCCUAGAUCCCUGGGCUCUUUCCUGUCAGAGCACUUACACUAUGUUGUGAUGGUUUUCAAAAAUUGUUAAAUAAAUGAAUGUAUAAUUACAUUAAUUAAAAUGGAAAGCCAUUAGACAUAGAAUCAGAA